GUUUCCGCUGGGCUGGAGAGCUCCAACUCUGCCAACCCGGACGAGGCAGGUGCCAGACCCAGUUCUUGCUCUCUCUGCGGCUCCAGAGAGGGGGUGGAGCUGCUGGGUCUCUGUGCCAGCCAGAGGCAGAAAUCAAUGCAUCGAGCUGGCCCCUGGGAUCCAGAGAGCCAGGGAGAGGAAGAUUUAAUUCAUCCCCAACCUAGAGCCCUGCCUCGGAGUCAGAUCCCUUGGGAGUCACCCACUUCGGUUAGCCAAGCUCAAAGGAGUCCCUCCCACGAAGAACUGGGGCAGACCCUGCUGGCUCCCUGCAAAGAAGAGCACUCCUCUGCACUAACCCAACUGAGACUGCAACCUAGCUCCCUGCCUCAGUUUCCUUACAUUGGGAGUGAAACACCAGGUCUGCAGCAUGCCUCCUUAGCCUGGAAAAGGAAAAAUUACAGUGGGAAAUAAGACAGAAGCUGGCCCUUCCUUUGCAGCCGGCUCACCAUGGUGCUCCAGGCACGACGCUGCCAAGUGUGCUCUGUGCCAGGGCCGAGGCCUGGGGUUGGGGGAGGGAACUGGGGACCCUCAGGCCAAUGGCUGCCAGUGGUCCUGGAGCCCCUCGCCUAUUCUGCAGAGAGCCUGAAACUUUCCAGGGAGAGGCACGGCUAGCCCUGCUGGGUGCACAGAGAGCCGAUGUUGGCGGGGAGGCAGCUGGCACCUCCAUCAACCACUCCCAGGCGGUGCUCCAGCGCUUGCAGGAGCUGCUGCGGCAGGGCAACGCCAGCGAUGUGGUUCUGCGGGUGCAGGCUGCGGGCACCGAUGAGGUCCGGGUAUUCCACGCCCACCGCCUGCUGCUGGGACUGCACAGUGAGCUGUUCCUGGAGCUGCUAAGUAACCAGAGCGAGGCGGUGCUGCAGGAGCCACAGGACUGCGCCGCUGUCUUCGACAAGUUCAUCAGGUACCUGUACUGCGGGGAGCUGACCGUGCUGCUGACCCAGGCCAUCCCCCUGCACAGACUGGCCACCAAGUACGGCGUGUCCUCCCUGCAGCGCGGCGUGGCCGACUACAUGCGCGCGCACCUGGCGGGAGGCGCGGGCCCGGCGGUGGGCUGGUACCACUACGCGGUGGGCACCGGGGACGAGGCCCUGCGCGAGAGCUGCCUGCAGUUCCUGGCCUGGAACCUGUCGGCCGUGGCGGCCAGCACCGAGUGGGGCGCCGUGAGCCCCGAGCUGCUCUGGCAGCUCCUGCAACGCUCGGACCUGGUGCUGCAGGAUGAACUGGAGCUGUUCCACGCGCUGGAGGCCUGGCUGGGUCGCGCGCGGCCGCCCCCUGCCGUGGCCGAGCGGGCGCUGCGCGCCAUACGCUACCCCAUGAUCCCACCGGCACAGCUGUUCCAGCUGCAGGCGCGCUCGGCAGCCCUGGCGCGCCACGGCCCCGCGGUGGCCGACCUCCUGCUGCAGGCCUACCAGUUCCACGCCGCGUCGCCGCUGCACUACGCCAAGUUCUUCGACGUCAACGGCAGCGCCUUCCUGCCCCGCAACUACCUCGCGCCCGCCUGGGGCGCCCCGUGGGUCAUCAACAACCCGGCCCGCGACGACCGCAGCACCAGCUUCCAGACGCAGCUGGGCCCGAGUGGCCACGACGCGGGCCGCCGGGUCACCUGGAACGUGCUCUUCUCGCCGCGCUGGCUGCCCGUCAGCCUGCGGCCCGUUUACGCGGACGCCGCGGGCACUGCUCUGCCCGCCGCGCGCCCGGAGGACGGCCGACCGCGGCUGGUGGUGACGCCGGCCAGCAGCGGCGGCGACGCGGCGGGCGUGAGCUUCCAGAAGACGGUGCUGGUGGGGGCGCGCCAGCAGGGCCGCCUGCUGGUCCGCCACGCCUACAGCUUCCACCAGAGCAGCGAGGAGGCCGGCGACUUCCUGGCGCACGCCGACCUGCAGCGGCGCAACUCCGAGUACCUGGUUGAGAACGCCCUGCACCUGCACCUCAUCGUCAAGCCCGUAUACCACACCCUUAUCCGGACCCCCAAGUAGCCUCGGGGUCUGGGAAUAAAGGCCUGGCCUAGGUGGUCCCUGUGGGUCUGGGAAGGGCAAGGCGAGCCUGGAGGUGGCAACAAGCCUGGUCCCCUGGAUGGCCAGGCGCCGGCCACCCUAGGGCUGGGGUGGAGUCCAGGUGAGGCGUGGUAGACAAGAUGCCUGGUUUCAAGAGCUGAUUUCACAGCUGACUUGAAGGAACGUUCUUGGUCCUGAAUAAACCGAUGCUCAGAGUGGUAAA